AUCAGCUGCCUUCCCCGGGCGUCUCCCCGCAACCUCCUCAACUUCCCUAGUCAGUGACGCGGCGCCGGCCAGAAAUCCGACCGGACCGGGCUCGGGGGAGCGUGAGUUGCAGCAUGUGCCGAAGCGCCACCUCAGAAGAUAAAAAGAAAUGAGUCUCAUAUUUGGCAUUCUUUUAGUUAAAAGAAGAUGGAUGCACAGUGUUCAGCCAAGGUCAAUGCAAGGAAGAGGAGAAAAGAGGCGCCCGGACCCAACGGGGCAACAGAAGAAGAUGGGGUUCCUUCCAAAGUGCAGCGCUGUGCAGUGGGCUUACGGCAACCAGCUCCUUUUUCUGAUGAAAUUGAAGUUGACUUUAGUAAGCCCUAUGUCAGGGUAACUAUGGAAGAAGCCAGCAGAGGAACUCCUUGUGAGCGACCUGUGAGAGUUUAUGCCGAUGGAAUAUUUGACUUAUUUCACUCUGGUCACGCCCGAGCUCUGAUGCAAGCGAAGAACCUUUUCCCUAAUACGUACCUCAUUGUGGGAGUUUGCAGUGAUGAGCUCACACACAACUUCAAAGGCUUCACGGUGAUGAACGAGAAUGAGCGCUAUGACGCAGUCCAGCACUGCCGCUACGUGGAUGAGGUGGUGAGGAAUGCGCCCUGGACGCUGACACCCGAGUUCCUGGCCGAACACCGGAUUGAUUUUGUAGCCCAUGAUGAUAUUCCUUAUUCAUCUGCUGGCAGUGAUGAUGUUUAUAAGCACAUCAAGGAGGCAGGCAUGUUUGCUCCAACACAGAGGACAGAAGGUAUCUCCACAUCAGACAUCAUCACCCGAAUUGUGCGGGAUUAUGAUGUGUAUGCGAGGCGGAACCUGCAGAGGGGCUACACAGCAAAGGAGCUCAAUGUCAGCUUUAUCAACGAGAAGAAAUACCACUUGCAGGAGAGGGUUGACAAAGUAAAGAAGAAAGUGAAAGAUGUGGAGGAAAAGUCAAAAGAAUUUGUUCAGAAGGUGGAGGAAAAAAGCAUUGACCUCAUUCAGAAGUGGGAGGAGAAGUCCCGAGAAUUCAUUGGAAGUUUUCUGGAAAUGUUUGGUCCGGAAGGAGCACUGAAACAUAUGCUGAAAGAGGGGAAGGGCCGGAUGCUGCAGGCCAUCAGCCCGAAGCAGAGCCCCAGCAGCAGCCCUACUCGCGAGCGCUCCCCCUCCCCCUCUUUCCGAUGGCCCUUCUCCGGCAAGACUUCCCCACCUUGCUCCCCAGCAAAUCUCUCCAGGCACAAGGCUGCAGCCUAUGAUAUCAGUGAGGAUGAAGAAGACUAAUGUUUCCUCCCUCCUUUCCUGUCCUCCCUUUCUGUCCCAUUACCUUCAGAAGCUCUCUGUUGAAUUCCAAAUUGUGACCCCAACACUAAACCUAAGGACAGCUACAAAGGAAAGACAACUGGGGAAAGAAGACCUAGGACUGGGGGAACCCAAACAGCCUGUCCUGCAAGUGACAUCACUCACCCACACGAAGGAGGGGGACUGCACCUUAGAAGCCUGCUCUGCAUCCAUUUACCCCCCCCCAAGGGCUUUGUUUCACUGUUUAUGUUCACGUGAUCUCAACAGGGAAAUUGUCAUUUUCAUUAAUUUUUUAAAAAAUUCGUCUUUCAAAUGUAGAACUAAUUUUUUGCCCCUGAGGAGUGGGCAGAAGAAGGAGGUAGUGUAAUACGCAGAGGCCUUUUCUUCCCGGUAUACUAUAGCAUUUGCCUUCCGUUCUGAAGCUAUGUGGCUUGCCAAGUCCUUCACGAAAUGAGCCACGCUGAUGGGUAAUUUGUGGAGAAAUAUCUUAAUUUUGAUUUCCUUAAGGAAAAGCGAAAAGCAGAGUUACAGUCACAAAUCCCCUGAACGUACUGCUGUCACCAGUGUCAUUGUGGCUGCGGGAAGGAGAUCUGAACCUAACUUUUCUUACUCCCUGAGGAGUUUCUUGUUGGACCCAAUGGGGUCCAUGAAGACACUGAUGGGGAUGGAAGCAGACCCAUGGCAUCAACUGCAGUGUUUCUGCUGUGUUCAUCUUCUCAGAAAACUCUGUGACCCAGUUCUUUGGGAGCUUUUGUCAGUCUCUUUCGUGCCAUCUACCUUCGAAGGAAGGAACACUUUUAGAGUUACAAUGAUGAGGAGAGGAGCGGGACAAUACUCAAUCCUAUACCAAGUCGAUUGAGAUUAGUUUCCUACUGGGAGUAAGUGCCUGGCCCUGCUACUCCUAUUUGAAUGCUAUUAAUAUUACCUAGCCUUUUACAAAGGAUACUUUGUAAAUGUCUGCUGUUGGAACUUGAUGUUAAUCCAUUUUGGUCAUAGCCAUAUUAGAGAGAUUUGCACAGAAUGUAAAGGCAAAAGCAUAGGAAACACCUUCCUUUCUAAAGCAACAGCCUUAUCACCUUGACCUCUGUCCCUCUUCAGAACAUUCUUCCCUGGAACCAGUGCUCCACAUCUUUCUUUUCCUCUGAGAGCUGCAGCUGGCAGGGACCUCCCUCUGCUGCUCCUCCAGCAAGCCACAGAGCAUACCCUCACGUGACAAGAGUGUGGUAGGUUUUCUCCCCACUUUUCACACACGCCUGGUGGUUGUGGUUCCAUCUGCCUUGUUGGCUUGCCCGGGGGGAUUCAACACUUGACUUUCAAAUCAAAGAAUGCUAAUGCUUAGCACUUGCUGUUGAGCAUGCUCUAACUUUUAAAGCCCUGGCCUCCUGUCUCCUUAGCUGCUUAGCUACGCGGCCUAGCAGAUCAUCACCCAUCAGUAAUCCUGUGGCUAGAUCCAGGGGAAAAUUGCUUAUGUCCAGGCCCCACCCCUGUCACUCAUAAAUACCCCUUGUGGGGGUGGAAUUUUAGUGUUUUCAGCUAAGAAAACCACAUUUUCUCUUUCCUUGCCUCUGCUAGGACUGUGAGCAUCUCAUAGUCCACUCCCUAAACACUUUCUGGUAACACCUAGUUUUCCGCCUGAGGGUCAGAGGCUAGAAUCAUUGCCUGCACAGCAGGACUACCUUGGUUCUUAAAACUUGGAUCACCCAGGCAAGGCGUGGUGGCUCACGCCUGUCAUCUCAGCACUUUGGGAGACUGAGGCUGGUGGAUCACUUGAGGCCACGAGUUUGAGACCAGCCUGACCAACGUGGUGAAACCCCAUCUCUACUAAAAAUACAAAAAUUAGCCAGGCGUGGUGGUGGGCACCUGUAAUCCCAGCUACUUGGGAGGCUGAGGCAGGAGAAUCCCUUGAACCCAGGAGGCGGAGGUUGCAGUGAGCAGAGAUGGUGCCGCUGCAGUCCAGCCUGGGUGACAGAGCGAGACUCUGUCUCCAAAACAAAACAAAAACCACACACACAUACAGAAAUAAAGAGAAAUAAUCAACUAGAAAAAAAACAAAACUUGGAUCACCCAGAAAGAGCGUCACAGAGGCGAGGGAGAAUGAAGCCUCUUGUUAUCCUGAUCGCCUAUGACAACGACAUUUCUAACUCUUCUUUGAAGCGCAGUUCUUACUCUUAAAUCUGGUCAUACAAGCUUUGGCUUGGAAUCCUGUCUGUCUUUGAAACAGCUGAAGUUAGUGUUUUCCUGUGUUACCCAGUGUUACAUAGUCUCAUCUUUGAACUUUUCUGCGUCAGCCUUCUCUCUUUGGGAAUGCUGCCUGUUUCUGUCUAACUUAUUCUCCCUGGUGUGGUGUGGCAGUGAAGUCUGUGCUGAAGCCCAUCUGCUUGGUUCCUCCAAGUGCACAUUAUGCAAGUGUAUUUGGAUAGACAGGGAGAUGCCCGGAACGUGGUUUUCCUCCUCCCUCCCUAUUGGAGCCAUACCUCCUAAAUAUAUUGUCUGGGUCCCAAAUGUUUGAGCCCUCUUCCUCUGCUCUCAGUGGGCUGCUCUUGGCAUGCCCUGUGCUUGGAACGGGACCUGCAGGCUGACAGGCCUCUGAGACUGCUAGGGCCAGCAAACGUACAUGUUAUUGGGAAACUCCCUUUCCCCUUUUGGUGAGCUUCUACCACCUCAGUCUAAUCGUUUUGACUGAAAGCUAUUUGUCUGACUGAAAGCUAAAAUCUUUUAUAGUGUGGCCUGUUAGAUACUUUGGGGUAAAUGUGGUCUGAGGUGCUGGACUAGCACGGGUAGAUGGAGAAAGCUGUUGGGAAGUUGCAUAAUGUGGUCAUCUGUGCCUAAUUAAAUGAGGUUAGAGGUGUGCACACCACCACAAUGCCUGGGAUCUAAAUCUUCAGAUAUUAACGUUUGAGGCUAUGGAGCUGUUUCCCUGAAUCACACACGAGAAAGCAGUCAACAUGGGUGGGCCAAAUGUGGCCAAGAUGAGAGAGCCAGAAGUGUUGGCCUUAGAGCAGAGCCUCUGUGUGUGAGACAUUAGAAGGCCAGAGCCGGGGAGGUGCCGGCGCAGCCACUGCCUUCCGGUGGGCCGGACGGAAAGCUUGGUCUUAUGCUAGAUUCAGAAGCACUGAAGAAUGGAGGUUGACACUUUAGAGGACUAGGAAGGGAUCAUUUGUGCUCUUGCAGCUAUUGCUGAUAGCUAGAGCCAAAGACCAUUAUAUUGCUGAGGCUUGGGUAAGAAAGUUAGGGAUGUGAGGAGGUUGAAAAUCCUGAAGAAGAGAAAAAAUAUGAGGGAGGCUAAGGAAACUUAGCCACUUUCUGAUCACUGAUGACUCCUUAGGCUGCACCUGAGUGAUGGUGGUGUUUUUGGAGGCUGUACCUGAGUGAUGGUGGUUUUUGGGGGGCUGCACCUGAGCGAUAGUGAUUUUUUUUUGGAGGCUGCACAGCUGGUCAGACCAUCUCUAGAUGUUCUUUCCACAGUGGUUCAUAGGGCGUCAUUCCCCCUUCCUGGAUUAUUUUGACUAUGGGUAGCUUAUUUUCAAGAGCUCUUUGCCUUUUUAAUCCUGUUCCAGAUCACUUAUCCAAAAUCUUUCCAAAUCAAUUAUAUUUUGCUGCUUUUCUUUAAUUCCCUAAAAGCCAUAGCUUCUAGAUUUUCUAUCAGCACACAUUCUCACCAGAAGUUGAACCAAUACAGGUAGAAAAAGAAAGCCCCCUUAAUGUUUUUAACUGAUGAUAUUUUUUUAAGCUUACCAAUAUAAGUAUUUUUAAAGGUUCUAUUUUUCAAAGUCAUAACAAUGAUUGUUCUUGUUUUCUCUCAUAGAAUAGACUGCCAUCGGAUAAAGAGUGGUCCCUAGCUUCUAUUUUUCCAAGUAAAUAAGUAGAACAUGUUCUUGGGAUUAUACCAUUAAAUGUUAAUUUUCUUGAAGAAGAAAGAUUGUUGUCUGCCAAGAUUUUAUGUUAGCGCUCGGAUUGAGGCAGAAAACGGAAGCACCAGGUUUAACACUGGGAUGACUUGGGUUGUGUUCCUGGAGGUUUGAAGUGGGCCUUCCCGCCUUUUGAGGGGGAAAACUGACUGUUUUGAACACAUAUCCUGGAUUAGUUGGGUUGUUUUGUAUUGAGGAUCCCUAAAAGACAAAAGAGUCUUGGAAAGGACUGCUGGCUUCGUCUUGAACGUUCGCCCCAUCACCAGUGUGAGUCCGUGGGGAAGUCUUCCUCAAGUGGGGUUCAGUCUGUAAUUUUCCUGUCUGUUCUUAGUUUGUUCUGAGUUAUUUUGGAUUUUGUUCUUUAGCCAAAUAAAGGCAGUGUGGUUUUACCUGA